AAAAAAAAAAGAUGGCCUUCUUAGAUGGGCGCCCAUAAAGAGACCUCAAGCCGGACUGCCUUCCUCAGCACCUCCUUAGCCUGCAAGAACACCAUAUAUCAUUGUGUCACCAAAUGGUAGAUAGAAAAAGAGCUUGCCUGGCCACUGCCCCUGCCUUGCCCCAGCUAACCUCCCACUAGGGAGAAGGUUUCAGUCUCUCUUCUCACAGGCACCCCAGCUUGCUCACCUUCUCCUGCAUGGCUGGUUCGGGGUUGGGCGUAGAUGCUGGACCAGUUUCCUGUAAACCCAGCAUGGAAGUGUUCAGCACCUGUCUUCCAAACACAUGGAUAUUCCUCACUCACGAUUCUCAGCUUUGAAGUGCUAGACAAAAGCUCUAUUUAGCUUCCUACUGUGUGCCCAUUCAUGGCAUCCUCUUGGGGAAUACUAGCAAGUCUUUCUGGGCACAAUGUGUCUCUCAGGCUGAAACUGCCAAGGGGUGCGGAAAACCAGAUAGAAGUGGGGAAAGGGCCAUUUCCCAGCUAAAGGCAGUUUCCUCCUCUAAGAUAUGGACACUUGCUCCCUUUAAGACGGAAUGAUUGUCAUUCCCAGGAAGAGACCUGAAUGGCCAAGACUGGCUAAUUUUUGUAUUUUUGGUAGAGAUGGGGUUUUGCCAAGUUGGCCAGGCUGGUCUCAAACUCCUGAACUCGUGAUCCGCCCACCUCGGCCUCCCAAAGUAUUGGGAUUACAGGCAUGAGCCACCAUGCCUGGUCCCUGGAGACUUUUUCUUUCCUUUUUGGGGGGAUUAUGGUUGGUUGGGGAGAAAGAUUUUUUUUUUUUUCUGUGUGUAUUUAAAAGUGUCCUGUGGUUUGCUCUGAUGAAUGGGUAAGUGUCCUUUAGCAGUCACUGAUGGGAGGUUGGCUGCUGAGGCCUCUGGGACUCUGAAGGAGAAGAUAUGCAGCUUCACUGGACCCUGGUUGUGUAUCUCCUUGAUUUUGCUCCUCAAAGGUUACGGCAAUGGUGACUAUCAGUCCUAAACAUUUAGUCCAGGUGUGUGAAAGCGAAACUGUGCCCCAAACAGUUAAAGACACCAAUGACUAACAGAAAUUCUUGAGUUUGCAGGAUGGUAGGUAAGCAAAGAAACAACUUGCUGAGAUGCUGAAAGUCCCUCCACUUGUAAGACAACAAAGCUGGCUAAAAUAGGUUGGAACCAAUGUGGCCAACUAGAGUCUGUGCAGUACCUGCUUGCUGACAUCACAGCCUGAAUUUCCACUGCGUGUUUCAUACUCACUCCCCCCGUACCUGCCCAUGUGAUCUAUGAGGUGUCAUGAAGAGAACUGCGCAUGCUGGAGGACUUUCCAGGCCUCCUCUUUCCUUCCACUAAUCACCUGCUAAUCUCAGAAUCCCGACACCUUUUCUAAUAAAAACACUGCCUUAGCACCAGCCCAGGGAGACAGAUUCAAGCUGGACUCCUGUCUCCGUGUCGGCCGGCCUAUAAUUACAAGCUUUUCUUUUCUCAAAAACCCGGUGUCAUCAUAUUGGCUUCUAGCACAUUGAACAGCAAGCCCCUUUCUGCCUAGAAACAAUCUGACCCUCAUAUUUACUAGUUUUCUCAACCUGUAACCAAGGGAAACAAAAAUGACCUCCUAAAUUUUUAACAAAGGCAAUCAACAUUUGUAGCUGGUAUGAAUAUUUGUUCUGUAAACUCAUAUCUGCAGGCAACAGAAUGUUUCUUUAGCCUAUGAGCCUCCAUCUUGCUGAGCUGAUUGGAAAUUCAUCUCAGCUGUUAUUGGGGCUCUUCUCAACCCAGAGAGUUCUGGGAUCUUUUUUUUUUUUUUUGAAAAGGAGUCUCAGUUUGUCACCCAGGCUGGAGUGCAGUGGUGCAAUUCUCUGCUCACCGCAACUUCUGCCUCCUGGGUUCAAGCGAUUCUCUUGCCUCAGCUUCCCGAGUAACUGGGAUUACAGGUGUGCGCCACUGCGCCAGGCUAAUUUUUGUAUUUUUAGUAGAGACAGGGUUUUGCCAUGUUGGCCAGGCUGGUCUUGAACUCCUGACCUCAGGUGAUCCGUCUGCCUCAGCCUCCCAAAGUGCUGGGAUUACAGGCGUGAGCCACCAUGCCCAGCCGAGUUCUGGGAUCUUAUGUAACCAAAACAAACCAAAACAAAGGGGUGCUCCCACCCUGCUCUUCAGUCUCACUGAUGGCUUCUGGGUGCUCACUGUGCUGUCUGCUUGGUCCCUUUGACCCCCAGAGUGCUGCUGCUCAAGAGUGGGGAACUCUAGGGGGGAUGAGGGGCCUAGGACCAACCACUGAGGUGACCUGCAGACACCCCGAGGGAGGUCUGGUGAAAGAGGAAGGAUCUGAUGCCCCAGAUACCAAUAAGAUUGCAGUGCCCUGCCCCCAAACAAGUGAAGAUUGAGCCAUAGGAAACUGCAAAAGAGCUGUAAGUAGGUUUCCCUGUGAUCAAUACUUCAUUUUUUUUCAAAUAUAUGAAAUUCUUUUAAUUUUUUUUUGUGUCUUAAGUGUCUGUGUUAGUCCAUUUUCUGUUGCUUAUAACAGACUGCUUGAAACUGAGUUAUUUAUAAAGAAAAGAAAUUUAUUUCUUACAGUUCUGGAGGCUGGGAAGUCCAAGGUUUAGGGAAUACAUCUGGUAAGGGCCUUCUUGCUGUUGGGAACUCUGCAGUCUCCCAAGGGGGCACAGGUGAGGGAACCGAGCAAGCUAGCUUGUCUUUCUUCCUCUUGUUAUAAAGUCACCAGUCCCAUUCUCAUAACUCAUUAACCCAUUAAUCUACUAAUCCAUGAUUGGUGAUUCAUGGAUUAACAGAUUACACUCAUGACCCAAUUACAUCUUAAAGGCCCCAUCACGCUACCACACUGGAGAUGAAGUUUCAACAUGAGUUUUGGAGAGGACAAAUAUUAAGCCAUAGCAAUGCUCUAAUUUUGUUGAGGUCCUAAGUACAUGCUGUACUGGUACAAGGAUGGUCUGCCUUGUACUAGGCCCUGUGCUGGUUUUCCUGUCCUGCCACUUUGGCCUCCCUUCCCCCAAGCAUGAAGCUUGAAGCCCUGUUCCUGCAAUCUGGCAGAGGAGGCUUCUAGCUUAUGGGGGAGAUGGGUCAGACCCCGGCAGCUCUGACCAAGGCUGGUUGGCAGGGGAGUGUCACGGAGAGACAGAGCAGAAGUGAGUGGGGUAGGGCCAAGCCAUUUCCAGCUGUGGGCUCAGGAAGGCUUGAAGGAUAGUUGAUAAAUGAGUGAUAUCUGGAAGGACAGGAGAAUUUCCGAGAGUGGAGGUGGAGCCCUCGUGUGGAGGAAACAGCCUGCACAAAGACAGGGGCAGGGGGGUUCGUGUGGCAGUUUUCCUGACCUGCCUUGCCCCUGGAGGCUACAGCCAGUUGUGUCCCUGGAGUAGAAUGCUGACCCUCACCAUUCCCAGCUCACCCCAAGGACCUCCCCACCCCAUUGUGACACUACUUCCUGGACACCAGUGGAGCUCAAAGGUUCUGCUUCCAAGGGUCUGGCUGGGCCUGGAUUGUGGUCAGGUGGGCCCUGGCUUUGGCUUGCGGUCCUGCCUACAGGGAGGCAGGGCCGGGAGGGUGUGGAGAGUAGAAAUUAUGAUGACCCCUGGCAAUUUUGCGGCCGCGUUCUCAGCACAGAUGGCAGGAGAGGAGAACUUCAAGGAAGAGCUCAGAUCCCAGGAUGCUUCCAGGAACUUGAACCAGCAUGAGGUAGCAGGACAUCCACAUUCCUGGUCUCUGGAGAUGCUGUUACGCAGAUUGAGGGCUGUCCACACCAAGCAGGAUGACAAGUUUGCCAACCUCCUGGAUGCGGUGGGGGAGUUUGGCACAUUCCAGCAGAGGCUAGUAGCCCUCACCUUUAUCCCCAGCAUCAUGUCGGCCUUCUUCAUGUUUGCUGACCACUUCGUGUUCACAGCCCAGAAGCCCUAUUGCAAUACCAGCUGGAUCCUGGCAGUGGGCCCCCACCUGUCCAAAGCUGAGCAGCUGAAUCUGACCAUACCCCAAGCACCCAAUGGCAGUUUCCUGACAUGCUUCAUGUACCUUCCUGUGCCUUGGAAUCUGGAUUCUAUCAUCCAGUUUGGCCUCAAUGACACAGACACAUGCCAAGAUGGGUGGAUCUAUCCUGACGCUAAGAAGCGAUCGCUGAUCAAUGAGUUUGACUUGGUAUGUGGCAUGGAGACGAAGAAGGACACUGCACAGAUCAUGUUCAUGGCAGGGCUCCCGAUAGGCUCUCUCAUCUUCAGGCUCAUAACUGACAAGAUGGGCCGCUACCCUGCCAUCCUGCUGUCACUGCUGGGGCUGAUCAUCUUCGGCUUUGGGACAGCCUUCAUGAACAGCUUUCACCUGUAUUUGUUCUUUCGCUUUGGCAUCUCGCAGUCAGUGGUGGGCUACGCCAUCAGCAGCAUUUCUUUGGCCACUGAGUGGUUAGUGGGUGAGCACCGGGCCCAUGCCAUUAUCCUGGGACACUGCUUUUUCGCUGUUGGGGCCGUGUUGCUGACAGGGAUCGCCUACAGUCUUCCCCACUGGCAGCUGCUGUUUCUGGUGGGUGGGAUACUUGUGAUCCCCUUCAUCUCCUAUAUCUGGAUUCUCCCGGAGUCCCCGCGGUGGCUGAUGAUGAAAGGGAAGGUGAAGGAGGCCAAGCAGGUGCUGUGCUACGCCGCAAGUGUGAACAAGAAGACCAUUCCUUCAAAUCUGCUGGACGAGCUGCAGCUGCCCAGAAAGAAGGUGACUCGGGCCUCUGUCCUGGACUUCUGUAAGAAUAGGCAGCUCUGCAAGGUGACCUUGGUGAUGAGCUGUGUGUGGUUUACCGUCAGUUACACCUAUUUUACGUUGAGCCUGAGAAUGAGAGAGCUGGGCGUGAGCGUCCACUUCAGACACGUGGUCCCCAGCAUCAUGGAGGUGCCUGCCCGGCUGUGCUGCAUCUUUCUCCUCCAGCAGAUUGGGAGGAAGUGGAGCCUGGCUGUGACUCUCCUCCAAGCCAUCAUCUGGUGCUUGCUUCUCCUUUUCCUCCCUGAAGGGGAGGAUGGCCUCAGACUCAAGUGGCCACGUUGUCCGGCCACAGAGCUGAAAUCCAUGACGAUCUUGGUGCUCAUGCUCAGAGAGUUCAGCCUGGCCGCCACUGUCACUGUGUUCUUCCUCUACACCGCUGAGCUCCUCCCCACUGUGCUCAGGGCGACAGGUCUGGGGCUGGUGUCUCUGGCCUCGGUGGCUGGAGCCAUCUUGUCCCUGACAAUCAUCAGCCAGACCCCCUCCCUCCUGCCCAUCUUUCUCUGCUGCGUCUUAGCCAUCGUGGCCUUUUCCCUCUCCUCCCUGCUGCCGGAAACGCGAGAUCAGCCCCUCUCCGAGAGCCUGAACCACUCCUCACAGAUAAGGAAUAAGGUCAAGGACAUGAAGACUAAGGAAACAUCAUCUGAUGAUGUCUGAGGAAGCGGCCAAGAAUGUCAUUCUCAAUGCCCAGAUCCUGAGAUUGGACCCAUACCCUGUCUCCAACCCUGCCUUGAAGCAAUUCAAUAAAGAGGAAGCAAACAGCCAGGCUCCCUGAGGGCCAGGCCCCCAGACCAUCUUGGGUUGGAAUUGAGUGGCCAAGUAUGGGGUCAUGGAUUCCAGGCCACAAAUUCCAGGCCUAGUUCAGUCUGGGGGCAGGGUCAGUCCUUCUCCCAGGCCAGCCCUUGACAUUAAAAAAAAUGCCCCCUCCUUCUGCAGGAGCUCUGCUGUGAUUCAUUCCAAUAAAGGUACAAUGUUGGUCUUGA